AGAGAGGUAACUUAACUUGCCAGAGUCACAUAGCUAAUAAUUGGAGUUGCGGAGCUACAACCCAGGCAGCCUGGAUCUAGUGUGUUCACAUAACCAUGGGCUUCAGUUUGUCUCCUACGUGGAAAGCUGAGCCAUGCCUAGUCGACCUGGGGUCGGGCAUCACUCCGUAUGACAGUGAAGGGCUCAUUUUAUCCGAACGGGAAGCAGGACAGCCAGGCUGCGGGGGGAACGGCGUCCCUCUGCUGAUGCCUGUGGCUGUGUUUGUGCAUUUACACGUCACAUUAGCGGAGAUGAAUGCCACUUGGAAUCCAACCCACCGCAGCAGAUUACCUCAUGCAAGAGAGAAAACAGCCCUGCCUGUGCUAGCCUGGCUCUGCGUUGGGCUGUAUUUACUCACGGGGCCUCAGCUGGCCAGGGCCUUGGAGCAGCUCUGGGGCCCCCGACCCGGGCAGGAAUCCCAGCUCAGGACUAGACGCACAGAGGAGGACGGGGUGGGGAAGAGCAGUUCCCUCCCAUACCCUCGUCCCCUCCCAGCAAGUACAGAGGGUCGUACAGCAAUCGUCCCGCCUUACUUAGAGGCUCUGAUCUGCACAAAACUGGCCAGAGCUGAAUUCAGCGCAAAUAAAGACUCGGCCCGCCGCCACUUCAGAAAGGUUGCUGACCGCUGGCUGGAAGCCGGCCUCGGAGAGUCCACAGCUGAGAAGCAUUUCUGAGCUGUCUUUAGUUAGCCCUGGGGGUUUCUUCCACCCUCUGGCUGUUUCUGCACUGAACUAGAAAAGAUAUCAAAGACACUCAUUAA